AGGUGCGCGGGUGCCAUGACGACUGCGCCUCACGAGCCCCCUCCUUCCCCUGGUCGGGAGGCGAGGGGCGGCGGGCGGCUGAGCCCUGCGGGCAGCAGCGCUGCGCGGGAGCCAGUCAGCCCGAGGGGAGGGAAACCGGCCAGGGCCCGGGGCCUGGGAGCGCACGCCCCCUGCUCACCUCUGCCCGGACCGACCGGACCUGCGGAGCGCGGAGGCAGGGGCGCAGCCCGCAACCAAGUGCCCGGAGACCGUCCCUCUGCCCGCUGGCCCGAAGGGGCCCGCUGCCUCCCGCCAUCGGAGACCGCCGGAGCCCGCAACUGGGGGCAUCAUGGAGGGGGAGCCCUCCCAGCCUCCCAACAGCAGUUGGCCCCUAAGUCAGAAUGGGACUAACACUGAGGCCACCCCGGCUACAAACCUCACCUUCUCCUCCUACUAUCAGCACACCUCCCCUGUGGCGGCCAUGUUCAUUGUGGCCUAUGCGCUCAUCUUCCUGCUCUGCAUGGUGGGCAACACCCUGGUCUGUUUCAUCGUGCUCAAGAACCGGCACAUGCAUACUGUCACCAACAUGUUCAUCCUCAACCUGGCUGUCAGUGACCUGCUGGUGGGCAUCUUCUGCAUGCCCACCACCCUUGUGGACAACCUCAUCACUGGGUGGCCCUUCGACAAUGCCACAUGCAAGAUGAGCGGCUUGGUGCAGGGCAUGUCUGUGUCGGCUUCCGUUUUCACACUGGUGGCCAUUGCUGUGGAAAGGUUCCGCUGCAUCGUGCACCCUUUCCGCGAGAAGCUGACCCUGCGGAAGGCGCUCGUCACCAUCGCCGUCAUCUGGGCCCUGGCGCUGCUCAUCAUGUGUCCCUCGGCCGUCACGCUGACCGUCACCCGUGAGGAGCACCACUUCAUGGUGGACGCCCGCAACCGCUCCUACCCGCUCUACUCCUGCUGGGAGGCCUGGCCCGAGAAGGGCAUGCGCAGGGUCUACACCACUGUGCUCUUCUCGCACAUCUACCUGGCGCCGCUGGCGCUCAUCGUGGUCAUGUACGCCCGCAUCGCGCGCAAGCUCUGCCAGGCCCCGGGCCCGGCCCCCGGGGGCGAGGAGGCUGCGGACCCGCGAGCAUCGCGGCGCAGAGCGCGCGUGGUGCACAUGCUGGUCAUGGUGGCGCUGUUCUUCACGCUGUCCUGGCUGCCGCUCUGGGCGCUGCUGCUGCUCAUCGACUACGGGCAGCUCAGCGCGCCGCAGCUGCACCUGGUCACCGUCUACGCCUUCCCCUUCGCGCACUGGCUGGCCUUCUUCAACAGCAGCGCCAACCCCAUCAUCUACGGCUACUUCAACGAGAACUUCCGCCGCGGCUUCCAGGCCGCCUUCCGCGCCCGCCUCUGCCCGCGCCCGUCGGGGAGCCACAAGGAGGCCUACUCCGAGCGGCCCGGCGGGCUUCUGCACAGGCGGGUCUUCGUGGUGGUGCGGCCCAGCGACUCCGGGCUGCCCUCUGAGUCGGGCCCUAGCAGUGGGGCCCCCAGGCCCGGCCGCCUCCCGCUGCGGAAUGGGCGGGUGGCUCACCACGGCUUGCCCAGGGAAGGGCCUGGCUGCUCCCACCUGCCCCUCACCAUUCCAGCCUGGGAUAUCUGAGGGGGUCCAGGGAGGGCGGGACGCUGCCUCAGGGCCCCGAUUGGACACGAGAUACAUGCAGGCGAUAGCGGCCUGGUGUGGUUAGGUGAGGAUGCGUGGUCCCUCCCUCUCCAGAGCCAGGCAGUGGUGGGCAGCUGCUGGUGAUGUCUUCUCUGCUGCCUUCACCCUCAGUAGAGGCAAAUGCGGGGGACGGGAAGGAACCAACUUGCCCUGUGUGGUGGGCUUGACAAACAUCAUCUCACUGAAUUGUCACAACGCUUUGGAGAUAGGUUGUCUUCUCUUCCUUCUACAGAUGCAAAAACUGAGGCCUGGAGAGAUGUGACUCACCCAAGUUUCUCAGGUGGAAAUGGCAUGUGAAGCUAUCUGACUCCAAUACCUGUGUGGUUUUUAUCAUCUCCAGCUGGCUCCAAGAGGGCCCGGUAAGGUAGAACACUGUGAACUGAGUAAGUCCUAAUUAGGCAGCUAGGAAGAAGCGAAAAGCAAAGCCGGCCUGUCCCUUGAUGCUUUGUGUCCAUGUGAGGGAGUCCCUCAUGUUCCGUUACUGAAGCCACUCCCCUUGAUCCUUUUCUAGAAGAACACGGUGUGCCCCCGCUGCCGGCUCUAAUGUGUUGGUUUGUCUUGUUUGUUCCAAGAAGUUCCAAGAAGCCAUUGUCCUCAGAGGACGGCAGCUUCAGAACGAGCCUUGGGGAGGCUGCCUCAGUUGCAGGGCACUCUAGGUCUUGCCCUCUGGGUCUGAGCUUAGAGAACAGAGGAGGGACUCCCAGACCAAGGCAAGAACUUACAAUGCCACAGACAUUGUAAUGCUGCAGGGCCACAGGAGGUGUCCUUUUACGUACUCAUAGACAACGAGGAAGGGGAAGCACGGUAUGCAUUUUCCACAUUGGGAAACACAUCUGCUCACUGGGGCUGCAGGUACAAAGCCUUGCCCAAGGUCUCUCUCCUCCCUGCUUCCUGGGAGGGAGAAGUUGGUCAACUGAAGCUGCAGCCGGAGUGCCAUUUGGAGACUCCUGAAGGACACACACUAAACUCUUCCCCAGCACAAAUGACUUGUGUACUCUAAGGAGGUACCAGGAGAGCCCUGUUUACUCUGGCUUUCCCCCAACACCCCUGCAUCAACUUGAAGAAAUGUGGCUUCUUUCCAGGAGACGGGAGCACAUGGGAUUGCCUUGGAGGGUCCUUUCACAGGCCCCUUCAUCUUGCACUUAAAUGGACAUUUCCCCCCACCUCUGUAGAAAACACGGUGUUGCUAGAAAUUUAGUAAACAAAAAAGAAACGUUUCCAGGGGUCGGGGCUCUGAGGCUCUGUUCCCUUAACCGACACACAGUGACUGUUUACUGUUUGCUCCACUCUAAGUUCCAGGUUUAGGGGCAGAAGAAAAUUCCUAAGCAGUUGUACAAUACAUUCUCCAAGCAUGUCCCCAGACACCGUCUCAUUUAAUCCAUAGUAAUGAGGUUGAAGGAGAUUGAAUGUUAUUGUCAUUUCACAAAGUGACUGAAGCUCAAAGGGGCCAAGUUUCCAGGGCCACAGAGGGGCAGGAUUUAGAUUAAAAUUUGUCUUCUGAUUGUUCUUCCCACCCCACAUGCUGCCUUUCAAGGAAGGUGGGGAUGACGGGAGAGCUGGUAAUUUCCCCAAAGGCUUUUUUGCCUAACAGUGAACCAGAAUGCCCACUCCUGGUGCCCAAGCUCUUGGUCUGGGAAAGAAAUCUAUUGUGUUUACUCUCGUAAUGUCCAGCCUGAGUUGUUCUUGCCCUGGUGCUGAGCAGGCUGCCAAGAGCCAUCAUGACCUUGUCCUGGUUCUGGGGGUGAUGGAUGAGGGUCUGAGAGAGAGUAUGCCCUCCUGCCCCUCAGUGGUAUUAGCUGGUGCCAUGCAUUUCUGGUACUGUAUCAGUGUCAUGUGUCAUAUGGGCCAGAGAGUUCCCAGCUGGUUCUGGGCUAUUUGUUGUGAAGAAGUCUGACUCCAGGCUCUAAAAGUAAGCCAGAGAAAGGGCCGUCUCAAACCCAAAAUGCCUAUCCCUAUGGCUGGGUGGGAAUUGUCUGAAGACACCACCUGGUGUCUCCUCUGGGGUGUGUUUCUCCUUUAGCAUAGCCUCCCCAAGUACAAGAUCAGCAUUUGAGGCUGGGGGCGGGUAGGGAUACCAAAGUACUCACUCAAGCCAACCUUUCCAUCACAGCCCCUUUGUCUUCCCCCAAAAGAUGUCAUGCUUUGAAAGGUUAUAACUGCCCAAAAAACUCCUUCAGCUCUCGCUGAAGGUUACAAUUAACAUAUUUUGCUGUUAUUUUUGUUUCUUCUAAAAAAUCAAUCAGAGGCUAUACCUGCCCAUUCAGAUCUGAGUGAUAACAGGCAUGACAAUGCUUUAAUGAAGCAGUGAGACAUUGUGGGUAUGUGGGGAGUUCGUUUCUUUGUGGAUGUGGUAAAAUAUAAAUAAUAUAGAAUUUACCAUUUUGGCCAUUUUUAAGUGUACAGGACUGGAAUUAAAUAUAUUCACAUUGUUGUGUAACCAUUACCACUAUCUAUUUUCAGAAUUUUUUAUUAUCCCAAACUGCAACUCUGUAUCUAUAAACAAUAUCACCGCAUCCCCUCUCCUCCUAGCCCCUGGUAACUACUAUUCUACUUUCUGUCUGUGAAUUUGGCCACUCUAGGUACUUCUAUACAAGAGGAAUCAUACAAUACUAUCCUUUUUGACUGGCUUCUUUCACUUAGCACAAUGUCUUCAAGGUUCAUCCAUGUUGUGGCAUGUGUCAGAAUUUCUUUCAUUUUAAAAGCUGAAUAAUAUCCCAUUGUCUAGAUAGUCCUCAUUUUGUUCAUUCAUCCAUCAGUGGACACUUAGGUUGUUUCUAUCUUUUGGCUACUGUGAAUAAUGUAUGGAGUUUUUAGAUGCUAGAAGUAGUUCCUGACAAUAGUGCCUGUGUGAAUCCUGAGGACAGAGACCCCAGGUUGGGAACCAGGGUCUCUCCCAACUUACCCUUUAUGGCUGACAAAACAGAGGCUUCCAGGACAGCUGUGAUGUGUCUCACUUCCCUGUGCCCACCCCAGCUGCUCUGGGCUUCUGCUGGGCUUUACUUCCUGACUAGAGUGGCUAGAAAAUUGUAUGUUUCCUCUACAAGAUGUUUUUAUGAAGCUAUUUUAUAAUUAUAGAUUUAUUAUCCUCACUGGAUUCCUAUGUUCUGACACCUGGACCCUGACGGGGCCUUGUGCAGCCUAGGCGCCCACGGGCAAGUGGUGUGGACCAUUCCUGACACGCCAUCCUCCACCUCCAGGUUGGCUGGGUUUCCUAAGGUGACUGCCCUUUCAUAAGCGGCAAGUUCGGAGAUGAACGGCAUGCGUGAUGGGGGAAAAGGGCCAGAGGCCUGUUGACACUGAGCAUCCCCACCCAGAGGGCCUCCUGGAGGGACUCUGUGUCCUGUCCUGCCAUGUGCGGCAUGAGUGGUCACCCUCAUUGUGGCUCUCCACUGAUGAAUGGCCUCUUGACUUUACCAAGACCAGGCAGCACCCAACAGACCAAUGUGAGCUGGAGGCGGAUGCCGGGCCUGCACCCCACAAACCACAGUCUGCCCAGCCCUGUGCUGAGGAGUCUCUCUUGGGGCCUGGAGGACUCAUGAGCUGAUCUGCAUUGGAAUGGAGGGCGAAGUUGGCAAAGGAAGAUGAGAGCCCCCCUAUCAUUAGUCUACUGUGUAUUCAUCCAAAAAGCAAGGCGAGAGCCAAGCCCAGAGCUGGAUGGACAAAGGAUUGCUAUUAAGCUCUGUACCUUUUUGCACCCGUUUCCUCAGCUCACCCCUCAGAAGUGUCACUGAUGAAAGAUAGAUGAGAAGGAGGCGGUCUAAAUGGGCUUCAUUACAAUGAACAAUGUUGAAUGAACAAUACAUUCCUUGUUGAAUAACCCAAUUAUUUAUGAUCAUGGCAUUUUAUUGUUGUUUUUCUCUCUCUCUACAAAAGCUCUACAUAAUCAUUGUGGAAAUUUUACAAGAUUUCAAUAAGCAAAGACAAGAAAAUGAAAAGCACCCAAAAUCCUACCGCAAGAGACAAGUAUAGCGUCCUUUUCUGUGCAUAUAUCUCUCAAUAUAUUUAACAUUCUUGGAACAGCUUUAUUGAGGCAGAACUUGAAUAUGAAAAAAUUCACCCGUCUUAAGUGUACUGCUUGACGAGUUUUAACAGUUGUAUAUAGUUAUGUCCCUACCACACUGAAGAUAUUUUCAUCAUCCUAAAAUGUUUCCUUGUGCUAAUUUAUAGUCAGUCCUUUCCCACGCUCCUGAUUCCAGAAAACGAUGAUCUGAUUUCAGAAUGUCAUGUAGAUGGAAUCAGACAGUUUGCAGCCGAGUCUGGUUUCUUUCACUUAAAAUGAUGUUUGCAAGAUUCAUUCAUGCUGUAGCAUGUAUCAGUAGUUUUUCCUUUUGAUUGCUGAGUACUAUUCCACUGUAUGAAUAGAUCACAUUUUGUUUAUCCAUUCAUCAGUUGAUAGACAUUUGGUUGUCACCAGUUUUUGGCUAUUAUUAAUAAUGUUGCCAUUAACAUUCAUGUACAAGUCCUUAUAUGUAUGUGUAUGUAUGUUUUCCAUUUUUCUUGGGUAGAUACCUAGGAUCGAGAUUGGUAGGUUGCAUGGUCUGUGUAAAAUUUAACUGUAUAAGAAACUGCCAAAGUGCUUUCCAAAGUCGCUCUACCAUUUUGUACUCCCAUCAGCAGUGUAUGAAUGUUCCAGUUGUUCUACAUCCUGGCCAACACUUAGCAGUAUUAGCCUUUUGAAAAUUUCCAGGCCAGGUGUGGUGGCUCACGUCUGUAAUCCCAGCACUUUGGGAGGCUGAGGUGCGUAGAUCACCUGAGGUCAGGAGUUCAAGACCAGCCUGGCCAAUAUGGGGAAACCCCAUCUCUACUAAAAACACAAAAAUUAGCCAGGCAUGGUGGCACACACCUGUAGUCCCAGCUACUUGGGAGGCUGAGACACGAGAAUCACUUGAACCUAGGAGGCAGAGGAUGCAGUGAGCCAAAAUUGCGCCACUGCACUCCAACCUGGGUGACAGAGCAAGACUGUCUCAAAAAAAAAAAAAAAAAGAAAGAAAGAAAGAAGAAAAGAAAAUUUCCCUGAUGACUAGUGAUGCUGGGCAUCUUUUUGUGUGCUUACUGCAUUCUUAUAUCUUUUAUUGUAAAGUAUCUUCAAAUCUUUCUUUUAAAAACAUGAUUUUGGCUGGGUGCGGUGGCUCACACCUGUAAUCCCAGCACUUUGGGAGGCCAAGGUGGGCAGAUCACCUGAGGUCAGGAGUUCGAGACCAGCCUGGUCAACGUGAUGAAACCCCAUCUCUACCAAAAACACAAAAAUUAGCCAGGUGUGGUGAUGUGCGCCUGUAAUCCCAGCUACUUGGGAGACUGAGGCAGGAGAAUCACUUGAACCUGGGAGGCAGAGGUUUCAGUGAGCCAAGAUGGCGCCACUGCACUCCAGCCUAGGUGACAGAGUGAGAUUCCAUCUCAAAUAAUAAUAAUAAUAAUAAUAUUUUAUUGUAGAGACUUUAGCACAAAAACUUGCCCUAACUCUAAGGGAUUUUUUUGUGAAUAUAAUUUUUUUUUUUUUGAGACAGAGUCUUGCUUUUGUUGCCCAGGCUGGAGUGCAAUGACGUGAUUUUGGCUCACUGCAACCUUUGCCUCCUAGGUUCAAGCGAUUCUCCUGCCUCAGCCUCCUGAGUAGCUGGGAUUACAGGCAUCUGCCACCACACCCAGCUAAUUUUUGUAUUUUUAAUAGAGAUGGGAUUUUACCAUGUUGGCCAGGCUGGUCUUGAACUCCUGACCUCAGAUGAUCUGCCCGCCUCGGCCUCCCAAAGUGCUGGGAUUACAGGCGCGAGCCACCAUGCUCCACCAAUGAUUUUUAAAUCCAUUAAGAAUGGGUCUAAAGCAAGGUAAGAGGAUAUAGUGUGAUAGAAGUAGGAGGGCUAUUUGAACAGAUGGUUAGGAAUGGCCUCUGUGAAGAGGUGAUGUUUGAGUACAGAUAUGAAGUGAGAGAGGGAGCCAUGUGACUAGCUGGGGAAGAAACAAACCCAGACAGAGAGAGCAUCAUGUACACAGGUUCUAAGGGAGGAGUGGGAUAACUGAAAAAGGAAUUAGUAGAUAUCAAAAUGCUAUUGAAUUUCAAUAAUUAAAUUUCUGGUUAACUCAAAACAUGUAUUCAGUGUCUAUUAAAAGCCAGGCAUAGGCCAGGCAUGGGGGCUCAUGCCUGUAAUCCCAGCACUUUGGGAGGCCGAGGUGGGUCGAUCACUUGAGGUCAGGAGUUCGAGACCAGCCUGGCUAACAUGGUGAAACCCCAUCUCUAUUAAAAAUACAAAAAUUAGCCAAGCAUGAUGGCAGGCACCUGUAAUCCCAGCUACUUGGGAGGCUGAGGGAGGGGAAUUGCUUGAACCUGGGAGGCGGAGUUUGCAGUAAGCCAAGAUAGCGCCACUGUACUCUAUCCUGGGCAACAGAGUGAGACUCCAUCUCAAAAAAAAAAAAAAAAAACAAAAAACAAAAAAAAAACGCCAGGCAUAGUACUACGUACUUUGUGUCUGUUAUUUAUUUCUCACAGUGGACCAUAAGCUCCAUGAGGACAGGAACUAUGUCUAUUUCACUUACCUUUGUGGAUUCAGGUAGGAUAUUGCCUGGUGCAUAGGAGGCACUCAAUAAAUGUCUGUUGAAUGAAUGAAGUAAUUAACUAAGCAGGUAUUUAUUAUUAUUCCCAUACAAUAGAUUGGAAAAGCAAGGCUCAGAGAAGUAAAGUAACUUACUGGAGGUUAUAUAACCAGGAGGUCCUGAAGGUGAGACUCAAACCUUAGUCUAUCUGACCACAAAGUCCAGGUUUUUGCCAUUCCCCAAGCUGCUGUGGUCUCUCCUUCCUACAUCUGGGAAACUGAGGUUCAGAGUAAAAGAAAGAGCCUUGAUGGAGGUCUCCCAUAAUCCUAAAAAUAAAACCAGCCAGCCACAGGCUCCAGGCUGCUGUUUUGGCCAUGAGACACAUUUGCAUCACUUUCAAUGGCUUCCAAAGAUUUGGGAUAGAAGGAAUACCAGCAGUUUAGGUAAAAGGUUUAAAUUUAGUUUGACUCAAUACCACAUCAAGCCCUCAAAGCAGCCACGGGCUCCCCUGCACUGUGGUCACUGAAGGAGCAAAAGCUGCUGAACUGGCUGUAGCGUCCUGCCUUGAGUUGUUUGUGUUCUCCUGCUAGCUGCAAUGCCCAGGUCUUUGAAUCCUGUCACCAAUAAAUGAUGCUGUUGUCAUGUGCAAGCAACCAAAUUAAUGUGGGUGGAAAAACCCAAGCUUAGUGAUUUGGGCAAAUUAGUUUAUCUGUCACAUAGCCAGUGGUGGUGUUAAAUCACUCUCUGUUUGAGGAGUAAUCACUCUCCCCCCAUCACCACCCUGUCUUCCUUUCGGUGUGGAAGUUAGAACAGCCAAGUCAAUCCGUUUCAGUGACUGAGCGAUCUACAUUUCUGUGUUUUGACUGCCCCCCAGGAGGAGUAUGUUGUGUAGUGCAUUUUGUUUGUCCAUAGUGCUGUCUCGUGGUCCUCCGAAGCCACCUCUAAUGAUCAUAAUUGCCUCUUUUAUUCUUCUCUAGUCCGUGUCUUUGCAAAAUGAUUCUGUUACCUAUGCUAUAAAUUAUGGAAAAUAAACUCAUUAUGAAAGA